GCGGUAGGAGUUCGGCGGACCGAGAGGUUCCGCGCCCACUUCGCGGCCCAGAGGACUGAGCCCGGCCUCCGGUGCAAGGAAACCCCAGAGGCCGGAACUAGAAUUGCAAAUUUUUUUUCACCCCGGAUUCCAACGGCAUUCUGUUAUAAGCAACAGAGAAUGAACGAAGACAGAAAAUUGGAACCAAGAAGUGGGAUUUUGCUGAUGACAAAUACCUGAAAAUGGGGAAGCAGCUUUGGAACUAGAGCCCCAACUUUUUACUGAGCACAAUAUAGCCAAAAGAUGACAUUGCCCAGCCUCUUUCGCAGAUAGCUGUGGCUAUUCCAGGAUCCCAGAAAAUGGUAGCCACAAAUGAAGGCCUCUGAAGCAGAACUGCCCUGGAUCUUUACUGUGCUGGUGCCCUCUCGGACUUUCUCUUGCCCUUCUGUCUCUGGCCUCUCAUUCUCCCCCGAGAAAUGGAAACUAGAAUUCCUCUUCCCCCAGCGAUUGUCAGUGAAACUUCAGAGGGCAAAGGGGAAGUUUUCCUUGGCCCCUCCAGUUUUGGUGCUGUGAACAGGAUACCAAAGCUGCUCUGUUCUUCUGGAAGCUGCAAUGAAGGGAACCAAGGACCUGACAAGCCAGCAGAAGGAGUCUAACGUGAAGACAUUUUGCUCCAAGAAUAUCCUAGCCAUCCUUGGCUUCUCCUCUAUCAUAGCUGUGAUAGCUUUGCUUGCUGUGGGGUUGACCCAGAACAAAGCAUUGCCAGAAAACGUUAAGUAUGGGAUUGUGCUGGAUGCGGGUUCUUCUCACACAAGUUUAUACAUCUAUAAGUGGCCAGCAGAAAAGGAGAAUGACACAGGCGUGGUGCAUCAAGUAGAAGAAUGCAGGGUUAAAGGUCCUGGAAUCUCAAAAUUUGUUCAGAAAGUAAAUGAAAUAGGCAUUUACCUGACUGAUUGCAUGGAAAGAGCUAGGGAAGUGAUUCCAAGGUCCCAGCACCAAGAGACACCCGUUUACCUGGGAGCCACGGCAGGCAUGCGGUUGCUCAGGAUGGAAAGUGAAGAGUUGGCAGACAGGGUUCUGGAUGUGGUGGAGAGGAGCCUCAGCAACUACCCCUUUGACUUCCAGGGUGCCAGGAUCAUUACUGGCCAAGAGGAAGGUGCCUAUGGCUGGAUUACUAUCAACUAUCUGCUGGGCAAAUUCAGUCAGAAAACAAGGUGGUUCAGCAUAGUCCCAUAUGAAACCAAUAAUCAGGAAACCUUUGGAGCUUUGGACCUUGGGGGAGCCUCUACACAAGUCACUUUUGUACCCCAAAACCAGACUAUCGAGUCCCCAGAUAAUGCUCUGCAAUUUCGCCUCUAUGGCAAGGACUACAAUGUCUACACACAUAGCUUCUUGUGCUAUGGGAAGGAUCAGGCACUCUGGCAGAAACUGGCCAAGGACAUUCAGGUUGCAAGUAAUGAAAUUCUCAGGGACCCAUGCUUUCAUCCUGGAUAUAAGAAGGUAGUGAACGUAAGUGACCUUUACAAGACCCCCUGCACCAAGAGAUUUGAGAUGACUCUUCCAUUCCAGCAGUUUGAAAUCCAGGGUAUUGGAAACUAUCAACAAUGCCAUCAAAGCAUCCUGGAGCUCUUCAACACCAGUUACUGCCCUUACUCCCAGUGUGCCUUCAAUGGGAUUUUCUUGCCACCACUCCAGGGGGAUUUUGGGGCAUUUUCAGCUUUUUACUUUGUGAUGAAGUUUUUAAACUUGACAUCAGAGAAAGUCUCUCAGGAAAAGGUGACUGAGAUGAUGAAAAAGUUCUGUGCUCAGCCUUGGGAGGAGAUAAAAACAUCUUACGCUGGAGUAAAGGAGAAGUACCUGAGUGAAUACUGCUUUUCUGGUACCUACAUUCUCUCCCUCCUUCUGCAAGGCUAUCAUUUCACAGCUGAUUCCUGGGAGCACAUCCAUUUCAUUGGCAAGAUCCAGGGCAGCGACGCCGGCUGGACUUUGGGCUACAUGCUGAACCUGACCAACAUGAUCCCAGCUGAGCAACCAUUGUCCACACCUCUCUCCCACUCCACCUAUGUCUUCCUCAUGGUUCUAUUCUCCCUGGUCCUUUUCACAGUGGCCAUCAUAGGCUUGCUUAUCUUUCACAAGCCUUCAUAUUUCUGGAAAGAUAUGGUAUAGCAAAAGCAGCUGAAAUAUGCUGGCUGGAGUGAGGAAAAAAAUCGUCCAGGGAGCAUUUUCCUCCAUCGCAGUGUUCAAGGCCAUCCUUCCCUGUCUGCCAGGGCCAGUCUUGACGAGUGUGAAGCUUCCUUGGCUUUUACUGAAGCCUUUCUUUUGGAGGUAUUCAAUAUCCUUUGCCUCAAGGACUUCGGCAGAUACUGUCUCUUUCAUGAGUUUUUCCCAGCUACACCUUUCUCCUUUGUACUUUGUGCUUGUAUAGGUUUUAAAGACCUGACACCUUUCAUAAUCUUUGCUUUAUAAAAGAACAAUAUUGACUUUGUCUAGAAGAACUGAGAGUCUUGAGUCCUGUGAUAGGAGGCUGAGCUGGCUGAAAGAAGAAUCUCAGGAACUGGUUCAGUUGUACUCUUUAAGAACCCCUUUCUCUCUCCUGUUUGCCAUCCAUUAAGAAAGCCAUAUGAUGCCUUUGGAGAAGGCAGACACACAUUCCAUUCCCAGCCUGCUCUGUGGGUAGGAGAAUUUUCUACAGUAGGCAAAUAUGUGCUAAAGCCAAAGAGUUUUAUAAGGAAAUAUAUGUGCUCAUGCAGUCAAUACAGUUCUCAAUCCCACCCAAAGCAGGUAUGUCAAUAAAUCACAUAUUCCUAGGUGAUACCCAAAUGCUACAGAGUGGAACACUCAGACCUGAGAUUUGCAAAAAGCAGAUGUAAAUAUAUGCAUUCAAACAUCAGGGCUUACUAUGAGGUAGGUGGUAUAUACAUGUCACAAAUAAAAAUACAGUUACAACUCAGGGUCACAAAAAAUGCAUCUUCCAAUGCAUAUUUUUAUUAUGGUAAAAUAUACAUAAAUAUAAUUCACCAUUUUAACAUUUAAUUCAUAUUAAAUACGUACAAAUCAGUGACAUUUAGUACAUUCACAGUGUUGUGCCACCAUCACCACUAUUUAGUUCCAGAACAUUUGCAUCAUCAAUACAUUGUCUAGAGACAAGACUAUCCUGGGUAGGCAGAAACCAUAGAUCUUUUGUGUUUACAGCUAUGGAAACCAACUGUACCAUAAAGAUAGUUCACUGAGUUUUAAAGCCAAGCCACAUCUUAUUUUUCCAAGGUUUAAUUUAGUGAGAGGGCAGCAUUAGUGUGGAGUGGCAUGCUUUUGCCCUAUCGUGGAAUUUACACAUCAGAAUGUGCAGGAUCCAAGUCUGAAAGUGUUGCCACCCGUCACACAACAUGGGCUUUGUUUGCUUAUUCCAUGAAGCAGCAGCUAUAGACCUUACCAUGGAAACAUGAAGAGACCCUGCACCCCUUUCCUUAAGGAUUGCUGCAAGAGUUACCUGUUGAGCAGGAUUGACUGGUGAUGUUUCAUUCUGACCUUGUCCCAAGCUCUCCAUCUCUAGAUCUGGGGACUGACUGUUGAGCUGAUGGGGAAAGAAAAGCUCUCACACAAACCGGAAGCCAAAUGUCCCCUAUCUCUUGAAUGAUCAAGUCACUUUUGACAACAUCCAGGUGAAUAUAAAAACUUAAUAAAGCUGUGGAAAGGAACUCUUAAUCUUCUUUUCUGCUACUUAGGUUAAAUUCACUAGAUCUUGAUUAGGAAUCAAAAUUCGAAUUGGGACAUGUUCAAAUUCUUUCUUGUGGUAGUUGCCUAUACUGUCAUCGCUGCUGUUGGUUGAGCAUUUGUGGUGUACCACGCUGUGUGCUCAAGGGUAUUACAUUCAUCUUCUCAUUUAAUCCUCACAACAAUCUGAAGAAGGUAGGUAUUACAAUUCCCACUUCAUAGAAACAGAAACUGAGGUUCAGAGAGGUUAAGUCAUUUGCCCAAAUGGCUGAGCCAAAGCCUACCAUGUACCUAACCUUUAUUUUCUUUCCCGAACAUACCAGGCUGUCUCCUCAUAACUUCCAAGCAUGCACUUAAAACUCCACAUGAAUACAAGGUUCAUGGGACUUGGUAUUCAUAGAAAGGGAGGCAGAAAGCUGGUCUGUUCCUGAUAGGCUUGUAAUUUAAUAUCAUUCUGUUCAUGUGCUUUGGAUGGAAGCACAUCUGGCAUAUGAUGCUAAUCAGUGGUUCCCAUACCCCUGGCUUCCUAAUUUUAAUGUUUGCUCACAGCAUAGUAGAUUGACAUCAAAUAGUGGCCGAUGAUGAUGAAAAUAAAGGUCAAAUAAGUUGAGCCAAUAACAGCCGCUUUUUUCCUUCUGUCUGCGUAUACAAAGCACUGUCAUGCACACAAUCUAUUCUGACCCUCACAACAACCCAUAAGGGUGUAAAUAGUAUUUCCAUUUUACAAAUGAGGAUCACACAAACUACUACAUGGCAGAGCAGAUACUCCAACUCAUGUCUUCUGGUUGAAGCCUAUUGCUUUUUCUUUUCUAAACACUUUCCCUCAGCAAGUUGGAAUUAGACUUCACAAGUCUCCUUCAGAGAACACAAAUCUUUUCUUAUUCCAUUCCUGUUUGGUUGCCUACGUCCAAUCUCCCCCUCCCCAGAGAUGCCAAAAAAAAAAUCCUUUAAGGUAUUUGGGAGCCAAACUCAACUUGUUAAAAUCUCAAAUUAUGGAGACAAUCAGCAGACACAACCUAACCCCAAUUAUUUUGGCAGGAAGGUUGGUUUAGAGGCAGAUCCAGCAAUCUGCUUUGGGCCACUCUGGGUGGGGUAGGUGAAAUAAGAUUGGUCACUGUUAACUAAUUUUAAUAUUGGAUUGGCCAUUGGUUAUCACUGAUUACCAUUCUCCCCUGGAUUUUCACCCAGGACUCAAAACUUGGUUCUGCUAACCCUGUUCCUUUAUGAGGAACCUUUUAAAGAUUCCUUUAUAAGGUGGGAGUUUUUUUUCUAUGAACCUAUAGGGGAGAAAAAAGAUCAGCAGAAGUCAUUACUUUUUUUUUUUUUUUUUUUUUUUUUUGAGAGAGAGUCUCACUCCAUUGCCCAGGCUGGAGUGCAGUGGUGCUAUCUCGGCUCACUGCAACCUCCGCCUCCUGGGUUCAAGCAAUUCUCCUGCCUCAGCCUCCCGAGUAGCUGGGAUUGCAGGUGCCCACCACCACACCCGGCUAAUUUUUGUAUUUUUAGUAAAGACAGGGUUUCACCAUGUUGGCCAGGCUGGUCUCCAACUCCCAAUCUCAGGUGAUCCUAUUGCCUCGGGCUCCCAAAGUGCUGGGAUUACAGGAGUGAGCCACCAUGCCUGGCCAGAAGUGGUUACUUCUGUAGACAAAAGAAUAAUGCUACUUAAUCAGGCUUUCUGUGUGACAAGAAAGAGAAAGAAAAUAAAGAAGUUUCAAUUCAUCCAAUUCUUAAUAAGAAAUAUGUAAAUAAAAUUUUUUAAAAUUACACUUCAUUUUAAUGUUGUAUCAGUCAAGGUCCCUGCAAGAGAUGGAUGGUAUGGUACACUCAAACUGGGUAACACAGGAGAGUUUUCAGAAAGCAACUAAAUCCAAAAUACUAUCAAGGAAUCAAUAUAAAAAUUGUUAAUAUUUUUCUCAUACUAAAUUUUCAAAAUAUUUUGUGUCUAUUACAUUUACAGCACAUCUUAAUUAGGACUAGCUGUGUGUUCACCUCACAUGUGGCUUGUAGCUACCAUACUGGACAGCACAUGUCCAAAAAAAUACACGUAAAGUUAAAGUUUAAAAGACACAGGAACUAAGCCCUCAUUGUCUUUCCCUUGGGAGGUAGUUUAAAGAGCUAUAGAUGCUGUAACAUUCUUGCUAUUAUUUAUUAUAUAUGACAUUAUUCCUAAAAAAGCUUUUGAGAUCCUAGGUUGUAUUCCUCAGGUUUUGUUGCCUUCCCAUGAAGAUGUGAAGGCAGGGAUGCCUGUUAUUCAGUCCAAGAUGCAUGACAAGAGACCUUGGGAAAGUUUCAUCUGGAUUUAAAGAUUAAUUCUUGAUGCUUACAUUCCAUACUCAAAAUGUAAAUUUGAAUAUUAAAAUAAAGAUGAUUUUUUUUUUGGAGCUAGUCUUGCUCUGUUGCCCAGGCUGGAAUGCAGUGGCAUGAUCAUGGCUCACUGCAGCCUCGACCUCCCAAGCUCAAGCAAGGCUACAGGUGUGCACCUAAGUAGCUAGGACUACAGGUGUGCACCACCAUGUCUAGCUAUUUUUUUUUCUGUAGAGACAGGGUUUUCCUAUGUUGUCCAGGCUGGUCUCGAACUCCUGCCCUCAAGCAAUCCUCCUGCCUUGGCCUCCCAAAGUGUUGAGAUUACAGGCGUAAGCCACUGCACCUGGCCAAGAUGAAUAUUUUAAUAGCUCACAGAACAAAGUUUGCCACAUAAUGAUAAAAUUACUAUGAAAAUAUAUUCCCUUUAUUGUCAGUUUAAAAGAUGAACUGAGUUUCACCCAAACUGGUCUGGCCCCUCUCUGAUUCAAAUACCAAUAGUUGCUCUGAUUCAAAUUCCAACUGUUAGAACAUGACAGCUGCUCAUAACUAGCUUUGCUUACUAACCAUGUUUCUUUCCAUUUGUAUUAGGUCCUUUACUUUUUAUAACAGCCUCAAAGUUUCAUGAAUUGCUGCAGUAAACAUUGAUUUUCAUGUUUGUGAGUCUGCAAGCCAGCUGGGCAGCUCUACUUCAGGUGGUAAGGGUGGAUCAGACCUAUUCCAUAUACCUCUUGUUCUCCUUGUCCAGUGGUUUCUAGGGAUAUGUUCUCAUGAUGAACCCCGCAGAGGCUCGUGAAAGUGAGAGGAAACUAGGAUGCCUCUUAAGGUCUUGGUCAGGAUGGGGUCUCCUGUCACUUCUGUCACAGGCUAUUGUAAGUCAUAUGAGCAAGCUCAAUAAAAUAUAAACAAGUCAGAUAAACAGUGGGAGGAAUGGCAAAGUCAUAUGGCCAAGGCCAUGAGUGAUUAAUUUUAACACAGGAAAAAAGUAAAGCAUUAAAUGCGAUUAUUUAAUAUACAAUGUCUUAUUAACUGAAAUAUAAAAUGUGUUUACUGUAAAAUAUAAUCUGUUUAUCUCACCAAAGAAAUAUUAUCUUUAAAAAAUGUCAUUACUUCUAAGACAUCAUCAGUCUGCAACUUCUUUCCAUAGCCUUAAUCAGGAUGCUGUGGCAGCUCCCACAUUAGCCUCGCAUUCUAAACUGGUAGAUGUCCUAGGAAACCAUACAUCUAUGUAUUUUUCUUAUUUUAUACGUUUAGGACAAUGUAUAGCUAAUUACCCAACUUUUUAUUUGCAUACAAAUCUAAUACAACUGAACACAAUCAGUUUUAUCACAGGUAUAAUGGAUUUUUCAAUAGUGAGGAGGUGCCUCCAUGAGCCUUCUCUUUAGAAAAGUGGCAUUCAAGACUCUUCAUUUGAAGUGAAGAUUGCUAUGUCUUUUGCAUUGCUCUAUUUUACAUAAAUUAAGUUAUAAAUUGACACUAUAAUCAACUGACACCAUGAUCAGUGAUGAUGAUCACCCUCAUCAGCACUAGAGUUGACUUGUUUUUAUAACCCCUUUGCAUGUAUGUUGAAUAGCAAAGUUCAUCAGAGAACAUGUAUUAGUCAAUGGUAAGUAAGAUACUCUCAUCUAAGAAAUAACAUCACCUCUUCUAAUGAAGUUCUAAGAAGAGAGGGAAGAAAAAGUCUUGGGAGCUAGUCAGGGAAUAGUGUGUAUUUGCAAUUACCUAAACUGAACUCUACCAUUACUCCUAACCCAGUUCCUCCUCCUGUGUUUUACAUGAUUAAUGCCACCCCUGCCUCAAUGAACCAAGAUCAGCUCCAUCACUGGGACCUCCCCAUUCUGCCUGUGCAAUAUUUUUCUUUUUUAUUUCUCCUUCUAAUAUUACUGUUAUUGCUCCAGUAAAGAGCUGUAAUAUAUUUUACCUGGACUGAUACCAGGAAUGGUGGUGUUGCUUCCAAUCUGUUGCUGCUAGAUUAAUCUUUGCAAAGCACAGGCUUAAUUUCAUUGCUGCUCAACUAAAACCACUGGUGGCUUUCCAUUGCCUACAAAAUAAAGUCAACCUCCCCAUCAGACAUUCAAGGCUUUCAAUGAUCCAUGGCCGCCAGCUCUCUCCAGGCUCAUAUCCCACUCCACUCCUCUGAUGUUUCCUACACUACACUACACUAUACUACACUACAGCCAGGUAGAAUGACUGUUCACCCAACACCACUCAGGUUGUCUUCUCAACUUGGAAUACUCUUGCACCUUCAAAGCUCAUUUCAAAUGCCCCUUCAUUUGUGAAGCCUUCUCCAAAUUUCCAAGUCAGAAUGUCUCUUCCUUGUGCUACCACAACCCUUUAACUGAGCCUCCAUUAGUGCACUGAGACCAUUCUGUUCAGUGUCUGGGUGAAGCUUCCUGGUGAAAAAUAUGUUACCUAUUUCUUUCUGAAAAGUUGGAUUCAGGGAUAUUAUCACGGACCUAAGGUAAUAGUUCUAGCCAACCUCCCUGUCCACUGCCAGGCCGACUACAAACCCUUCUGUUGCUGGCGAGCUGGUCCGCACCACUAGUUCUGCUUCACUCUAUUUAUCUCUUGAUGUAACCAUCUUCUUUCUCCAGGUUUUAAGAACCAGCCCAACUCCUGGUUCCCUGAUGAAGCUUUUAUUCCCCUAGCCACAUGGAACUUUUCCUUUUUGGAACAUGCCUUUAGUUUCUGUGUAGUUUGCCAUGCAGCACUUCAUUGUACACAUUAUUAAAACAGAAUUUUAAGGAUUAGAAUGAACCUUAAAAGAUCAUGCAUCUCAAAAUUUAAUGUACAUACAAAUUACCCAGGGAUUUUGUUGAAAUAAAAAUUAUUUAAUUUUAAUUAAUAUAAAUAAUUCAGUAGGUCUGGGGUGAGGCCUGAGGUUUUACAUUUCCAACAAGCUGCCAGGUAAAGCCAAUACAUCUGUCCAGGAAUCACACUUUGCGUAUCAAAGGUCUAGAUGACAUUAUCAUUCCAAAGAGUUUCUUUUACAGGCUCUCAGAUCAGUGUUCAUCCACUACCUGACUACUGUCAUUCACAGGCAUUCUGUUCCACAGCAGGCCAGCUAACGUGGUAUUUACAAAGCUCACUCCUCUUAUACAACAAUCCAAGUGUUUCUUUUGUCAGUUGUCUGUGCCCCAGGAGAUCCCUCUCUGCCUUGCCUUGCCCUCUGCCUUUGGAGACCAGCACCUCAUACUCAGUGAAGGCCUGGAGUGCUUAAGAGGGAUUUCUUCCAGCUCUCUUGCCCUGGUCUUCAGUGUAUUAGAUGUAUUACCUCCAUGCUCUCAGUAGAGGCCCAUAGGAAAGAGUAGGUAGGUUAUGCCAGCUCACACGCAUCCUUUAAAAAUGGUUUAGAAGUUUAGCUGGUUUCUUAUUACUCCUGUCUAUGGAUGUUUCCUUCUGUCACUCUACUAGGGAUGAAACAGCUAAUCAUGUUCAAUAGUUACAUUUAGAUUGGUUUUUAAAAACUAUGAUUGUAUUAGUUCGUUUCCAUGCUGCUGAUAAAGACAUAUCUGAGACUGGAAACAAAAAGGGUUUAAUUGGACUUACAGUUCCACAUGGCUGGGGAGGCCUCAAAAUCAGGUGGGAGGCAAAAGGUACUUCUUACGUGGUGGCAUCAAGAGCAAAAUGAGGAAGAAGCAAAAGCAGAAACUCUUCAUAAACCCACCAGAUCUUGUGGGACUUAUUAUCACGAGAAUAGCACAGAAAAGACUGGCCUCCAUGAUUCAAUUACCUCCCACUGCGUCCCUCCCACAACAUGUGGGAAUUCUGGGAGAUACAAUUCAAGUUGAGAUUUGGGUGGGGACACAGCCAAACCAUAUCAUUCCUCCCUGGGCUCCUCCAAAUUUCAUAAUCCUCACAUUUCAAAACCAAUCAUUCCUUCCCAACAGUUCCCCAAAGUCUUAACUCAUUUCAGCAUUAACCCAAAAGUCCACAGUCCAAAGUCUCAUCUGAGACAAGGCAAGUCCCUUCCACUUACAAGCCUGUAAAAGCAAGCUAGUUACCUCCUAGAUACAAUGGGGGGUACAGGUAUUGGGUAAAUACAGCUGUUCCAAAUGAGAGAAAUUGGCCAAAACAAAGGGGUUACAGGGUCCAUGCAAGUCUGAAAUCCAGUGGGGCAGUCAAAUUUUAAAGCUCCAUAAUGAUCUCCUUUGACUCCAUGUCUCACAUUCAGGUCAUGCUGAUGCAAGAGAUAGGUUCCCAUGGUCUUGUGCAGCUCCGCCCCUGUGGCUUUGCAGAGUACAGCCUCCCUCCUGGCUGCUUUCUCAGGCUGAUGUUGAGUGUCUGUAGCUUUUCCAGGCACAAGAUGCAAGUUGGUGGUUGAUCUACCAUUCUGGGGUCUACCAUUCUGGGGUCUACCGUUCUGGGACUGUGGCCUUCUUCUCACAGCUCCACUAGGCAGUGCCCCAACAGGGACUCUGUGUGGGGGCUCUGCCCCACAUUUCCCUUCCACACUGCCCUAGGAGAGGUUCCCCAUGAGGGCUCUGCCCCUGCAGCAAACUUUUGCCUGGACAUCCAGGUGUUUCCAUAUAUAUUCUGAAAUCUAGGCAGAGGUUCCCAAAUCUCAAUUCUUGACAUCUCUGCACCCACAGGCUCAACAUCACAUGGAAGCUGCCAAUGCUUGGGGCCUCUACCCUCUGAAGCCACAGCCCAAGCUCUAUGUUGGCUCCUUUCAGCCAUGGCUGGAGCAGCUGGGACACAGGGCACCAAGUCCCUAGGCUGCACACAGCACAGAGACCCUGGGCCCAGCCCACAAAACCACUUUUUCCUCCUGGGCCUCUGGGCCUGUGAUGGGAGGGGCUGCCAUGAAGGUCUCUGACAUGACCUGGAGACAUUUUCCCCAUGGUCUUGGGGAUUAACAUUAGGCUCCUUGCUGCUUAUGCAAAUUUCUGCAGCCAGCUUGAAUUUCUCCUUAAAAAAAAUGGGUUUUUCUUUUCUACUGCAUCAUCAGGCUGCAGAUUUUCCACAUUUAUGCUCUUGUUUCCCUUUUAAAACAGAAUGUUUUUAACAGCACCCAAGUCACCUUUUGAAUGCUUUGCUGCUUAGAAAUUUAUUCCACCAGAUACCCUAAGUCAUCUCUCUCAAGCUCUAAGUUCCACAAAUCUCUAGGGCAAGGGUGAAAUGCUGCCAGUCUCCUUGCUAAAACAUAACAAGGGUCACCUUUACUUCAGUUCCCAACAAGGUCUUCAUCUCCAUCUGAGACCACCUCAGCCUGGACCUUAUUGUUCAUAUCACUAUCAGUAUUUUUGUCAAUGCCAUUCACAGUCUCUAGGAGGUUCCAAACUUUCCUACAUUUUCCUAUCUUCUUCUGAGCCCUCCAGAUUAUUUCAACACCCAGUUCCAAAGUUGCUUCCACAUUUUCGGGUAUCUUUUCAGCAAUGCCCCACUCUACUGGUACUAUUAGUCCAUUUUCAUGCUGCUGAUAAAGACAUACCUGAGACUGGGAACAAAAAGAGGUUUAAUUGGACUUAUAGUUCCACCUGGCUGGGGAGGCCUCAGAAUCAUGGCAGGAGGUGAAAGGCAUUUCUUACACGGCAGCAGCAAGAGAAAAAUGAAGAAGCAGCAAAAGCAGAAACCCCUGAUAAAACCAUCAGAUCUCGUGAGACUUAUUCACUAUCACAAGAAUAGCAUGGGAAAGACCAGCCCCCUUGAUUCAAUUACCUCCCCCUGGGUCCUGUGGGAAUUCUGGAAGGUACAAUUCAAGUUGAGAUUUGGGUGGGGACACAGCCAAACCAUAUCAAUGAUUUUGUACUUUAACCAGCUGAAUGGAAGUACAAUCUCUUGCUAUAUGACACAAUAAUUAUUUGCAAAAUGAGUAAACAUAUCAUAAGGAAAUUAUUUUUACAAGGUUUGAAACCUGAAAUGCAGUCUAUUAUCAUACAUAACUAAAAAUAGAGCCUCAAUAAACAGAUUCCCAGUUUUGAAAAUGCAACAUUUGUACUCCACAUUGUCAGUUUUCUUAGGUAUAUUUAUAAAUACUCCUAUAAAAAUGUAAAGAAACACAUAAUGUAGAUUGCUAAUUUUAUAAUAACACAAGUUGAUUUUGACAUCCAACUUAUUAAUUAUGAAAUGACUUUUGGCCUAGUAACAAUGAAAAUGGGGGCAAAUACAGAUAAAUGGUAAUUCUUAGAAUGAACUACUCAGCACCAAUUCUAAGUUUUUCUUGAUGGUAAAUCAUAAUGUUCCCUUUCUCCUCGGUUCUGCAAUCUAUAGGCAUACCAUAAUUGUAAUCAAUAGCUUAAAAAUAUGUCUCUCUGUCCUAUUCUGUAUCUGUAUCUCUUGGAUUUUUACCUUUGCAAUAGUCAACUGAACCAUCUUCUUGGAGUACUCAUGAAGAUGGAAGUCUACAUGGAGAAUACAGGAUGAAUCCACUCUGUCUCCUGCAGUGAAGUCUGUUUGAAGGAUGUAUUUGGCUGUCUUCUGGACAGGCCAUUCUAAUAACAGAAACAAACAAGUUAUUUUAAAACUUAUUGGAAUAUUCAAAUAUUAACCAAAGUAGAAAAAUAUAAUACACAUCCAUGUGCCCAUCACAGAACUUCACUGAUUAUCAUCAUUUAGCCAGUCUUGAAGAAGCAAGUGCUAAUUACAAUCACAAAUGAAACAAGAUUCAGACUUCAUGAAGAGCACUGCGCUAUAAUAAAAGAAGAAAUGAGCACAUACAUUCUUUUACUGACAGUCAAAUGGUGAAGGUGGGCAGAAUCAUUAUGUGAUGCAACAUGGCAAAAGUAUACAGACAGUGCAUCCAGAGGAAGGCACCUUGCUGAAUGACUAGAAUGGAAGUAGGAGACAUUUUGCAGGCCCCCUUCAUCCUGCAGGGAGAACCAGAACCACAGCAGCUCUAUUUGCCUAUUCCUCUUUAAAUUACAAAGUUAAAAUUUGGGAGUAGUAGAAAAUCAAUUGGUUAUCUUAUAGAGUCUCCUAGAAUAUUUCAUUGGCAUUGAGAAGGUGGAAAAUGCAAAUUAUAUACUUUAAAAUGUAAUUUUUGCUUUUCACAUAUGCUUAAAGCCUAAAACCUCUUAAUAAACUUCUUCUGAAAUAUA